GAGACGCUCAAGAGAGCAAGAUGUUCUCCUGUUGCUUCCCCACUUCGAGAGGUUGCUGCUUCAGGAAUGGAGGGAGUGAGAGCCUUUUCCGACAAUGCCGAAGAAGGCUCAUCCCUCACCCCAGACGCCUGUGGCCCUUUGUAAGAAGGCGCACCCAGGUACCACAGGACAGCCCGGGGCAGGCCCUAGCUGGCCAGGCCACACCAGAGAUCCCAUCGGGGCUGCCUCUGCACAUUGUCCUUGUCCAGGAGGAGAUUCGGGAGCCCAUGGAGGCACAGACACAUGCUCCUGGUCCGUACGCAGACAUAGCAGCACUUGCGGCACCGGCUGUCGAGCCAAAGCCAGCAUGGGAAGAGCCCCCUCCAGAGAGAGCGCUGGAGGUGGAGGGAGCUCCAGCCAAGGACCAGCCCAGCCAGGAGCUGCCUGAAAUCAUGGCACCUACUGUAGCCACUGGCCUUAAUGCUGGAGCUGAAAACGUGGCUGGAGAGAGAAGUGGGAGGGAGGGGGUGACAAGCACAGCCCCAGCCAGCAGAUCCCAUGCUGCCCCUAGUCCUGGGCAUGGUGGCAAACAUGGAGGCGGAGACCAGGGCAUUCAGACUGGACUCCUGUACCUCGCUGGAGAGAGGCUUCUCUCAUUCGCCGGAACCACAGCCCUGCUGCUGCAGGGCCUGUUUAUUGUGCUAAUUCUGGUGGGGUAUAUCUCUGUGAAGGUGAUGCUCAAGAGCAUUAAAACAAGGCUGGGAAGAAGAGUUCCAGCAGCUCCUCCUGCUCUCAGACGCAAUCUUCUCCUCCAGGCAUGGAAGUGUGUCUGCAACUGGGCAUCCAGGCUGUUUGCCCCUAAUGUGCUGCCCCGAACGGGCUCUUAACAGGUGGGCAGGGGUUGAGGGGACCAGGAGGUGGCUCCAAAGGGUACAGCAAGGAAAGCUUUUAAAGACAGCUGUUGUGCUCCAGGCUCUCCAUGCCACCACCUGCCCUAGCAUUUAUUAAUAGUGUUAGAAUUACAAGUUUAUGAAAUGAAAUAUAAAUAAAGUUUGAUUUCUGAAACUUC